AGUUGUCUCUGCCGCUGGGGAAGGUAAAGCGGCGACGGCGUCCUCAGGAGCUGUGGGGUCCCCUGCUAGAAGUGGGGGACUCGGCGGGGGAGUCAUUUAAUACUUCAUGAUUAGAACAAAUAUGUGAAAGUUCCCACCAACCAGUGAGAAUUUCUUCCUUCAGACGGUUUUGGAUCUUACUGCACAGCUUUCUGAGAAGUUCUUUUGGUGCCAUGUUUUGUGGCUUGCAUCAAAAGAGGAGUUUGUCUUCAUGAAGAUUCCUAACAUUGGUAAUGUGAUGAAUAAAUUUGAGAUCCUUGGGGUUGUAGGUGAAGGAGCCUAUGGAGUUGUACUUAAAUGCAGACACAAGGAAACACAUGAAAUUGUGGCGAUCAAGAAAUUCAAGGACAGUGAAGAAAAUGAAGAAGUCAAAGAAACGACUUUACGAGAGCUUAAAAUGCUUCGGACUCUCAAGCAGGAAAACAUUGUGGAGUUGAAGGAAGCAUUUCGUCGGAGGGGAAAGUUGUACUUGGUGUUUGAGUAUGUUGAAAAAAAUAUGCUCGAAUUGCUGGAAGAAAUGCCAAAUGGAGUUCCACCUGAGAAAGUAAAAAGCUACAUCUAUCAGCUAAUCAAGGCUAUUCACUGGUGCCAUAAGAAUGAUAUUGUCCAUCGAGAUAUAAAACCAGAAAAUCUCUUAAUCAGCCACAAUGAUGUCCUAAAACUGUGUGACUUUGGUUUUGCUCGUAAUCUGUCAGAAGGCAAUAAUGCUAAUUACACAGAGUACGUUGCCACCAGAUGGUAUCGGUCCCCAGAACUCUUACUUGGCGCUCCCUAUGGAAAGUCCGUGGACAUGUGGUCGGUGGGCUGUAUUCUUGGGGAGCUUAGCGAUGGACAGCCUUUAUUUCCUGGAGAAAGUGAAAUUGACCAACUUUUUACUAUUCAGAAGGUGCUAGGACCACUUCCAUCUGAGCAGAUGAAGCUUUUCUACAGUAAUCCUCGCUUCCAUGGGCUCCGGUUUCCAGCUGUUAACCAUCCUCAGUCCUUGGAAAGAAGAUACCUUGGAAUUUUGAAUAGUGUUCUACUUGACCUAAUGAAGAAUUUACUGAAGUUGGACCCAGCUGACAGAUACUUGACAGAACAGUGUUUGAAUCACCCUACAUUUCAAACCCAGAGACUUCUGGAUCGUUCUCCUUCAAGGUCAGCAAAAAGAAAACCUUACCAUGUGGAAAGCAGCACAUUGUCUAAUAGAAACCAAGCCGGCAAAAGUACUGCUUUGCAGUCUCACCACAGAUCUAACAGCAAGGACAUCCAGAACCUGAGUGUAGGCCUGCCCCGGGCUGACGAAGGUCUCCCUGCCAAUGAAAGCUUCCUAAAUGGAAACCUUGCUGGAGCUAGUCUUAGUCCACUGCACACCAAAACCUACCAAGCAAGCAGCCAGCCUGGGUCUACCAGCAAAGAUCUCACCAACAACAACAUACCACACCUUCUUAGCCCAAAAGAAGCCAAGUCAAAAACAGAGUUUGAUUUUAAUAUUGACCCAAAGCCUUCAGAAGGCCCAGGGACAAAGUACCUCAAGUCAAACAGCAGAUCUCAGCAGAACCGCCACUCAUUCAUGGAAAGCUCUCAAAGCAAAGCUGGGACACUGCAGCCCAAUGAAAAGCAGAGUCGGCAUAGCUAUAUUGACACAAUUCCCCAGUCCUCUAGGAGUCCCUCCUACAGGACCAAGGCCAAAAGCCAUGGGGCACUGAGUGACUCCAAGUCUGUGAGCAACCUUUCUGAAGCCAGGGCCCAAAUUGCGGAGCCCAGUACCAGUAGGUACUUCCCAUCUAGCUGCUUAGACUUGAAUUCUCCCACCAGCCCAACCCCCACCAGACACAGUGACACGAGAACUUUGCUCAGCCCUUCUGGAAGAAAUAACCGAAAUGAGGGAACGCUGGACUCACGUCGAACCACAACCAGACAUUCUAAGACGAUGGAGGAAUUGAAGCUGCCGGAGCACAUGGACAGUAGCCAUUCCCAUUCACUGUCUGCACCUCACGAAUCUUUUUCUUAUGGACUGGGCUACACCAGCCCCUUUUCUUCCCAGCAACGUCCUCAUAGGCAUUCUAUGUAUGUGACCCGUGACAAAGUGAGAGCCAAGGGCUUGGAUGGAAGCUUGAGCAUAGGGCAAGGGAUGGCAGCUAGAGCCAACAGCCUGCAACUCUUGUCACCCCAGCCUGGAGAACAGCUCCCUCCAGAGAUGACUGUGGCAAGAUCUUCGGUCAAAGAGACCUCCAGAGAAGGCACCUCUUCCUUCCAUACACGCCAGAAGUCUGAGGGUGGAGUGUAUCAUGACCCACACUCUGAUGAUGGCACAGCCCCCAAAGAAAAUAGACACCUAUACAAUGAUCCUGUGCCAAGGAGAGUUGGUAGCUUUUACAGAGUGCCAUCUCCACGUCCAGACAAUUCUUUCCAUGAAAAUAAUGUGUCAACUAGAGUUUCUUCUCUACCAUCAGAGAGCAGUUCUGGAACCAACCACUCAAAAAGACAACCAGCAUUCGAUCCAUGGAAAAGUCCUGAAAAUAUUAGUCAUUCAGAGCAACUCAAGGAAAAAGAGAAGCAAGGAUUUUUCAGGUCAAUGAAAAAGAAAAAGAAGAAAUCUCAAACAGUACCCAAUUCCGACAGCCCUGAUCUUCUGACGUUGCAGAAAUCCAUUCAUUCUGCUAGCACUCCAAGCAGCAGACCAAAGGAGUGGCGCCCCGAGAAGAUCUCAGAUCUGCAGACCCAAAGCCAGCCAUUAAAAUCACUGCGCAAGUUGUUACAUCUCUCUUCGGCCUCAAAUCACCCGGCUUCCUCAGAUCCCCGCUUCCAGCCCUUAACAGCUCAACAAACCAAAAAUUCCUUCUCAGAAAUUCGGAUUCACCCCCUGAGCCAGGCCUCUGGCGGGAGCAGCAACAUCCGGCAGGAACCCGCACCGAAGGGCAGGCCAGCCCUCCAGCUGCCAGGUCAGAUGGAUCCUGGUUGGCAUGUGUCCUCUGUGACCAGGAGUGCCACAGAGGGCCCUUCCUACUCUGAACAGCUGGGUGCCAAAAGUGGGCCAAAUGGGCACCCCUAUAACAGAACAAAUCGCUCACGAAUGCCAAAUCUGAAUGAUUUAAAAGAGACAGCCUUGUAAUUUGUGCUGGUAGGGGGGAGGGGUGGACAGACAAGCCAGUGGGGAGGGGUGGGAAAGGGUGGGCUGGGCUUGGGGCAUGGGCCGGGCCAAGUGGUGAGCCAAUAUUUUCAGCUUUAUGAAGGUGUGUGCAAUAUUGCAUGUGUUGGGGCCGUUGAGCUCCUCGCGGCCACAAAUGCUAGUCAGGGAUCUUAGAGCCACAGGAGUUCCUUAGGGAUCGCCACUCCCCACAGGUCUUGUGUGAGAAUAGAUAGAGUGUGCCAUUGAGGAAGAAGAAAUUCUUGCCAGUUUCUCCCCUUUACAUUCCAGCUUUAGUGCAAUCUCUGUUGAACUUGGGAAUGCCAGGAUGUGUCCUGGCACUGCAAGGGAUAGGAAAGUCGUGUUGACCGAUGCCCUUACUACAUAUUUUUUUCUGCCUAGAGUAAAUGUGGGGUUUAUUGUAAUCCAAGAGUAUCCCUUUGAAGGGUUAGCAGAUGAACUGUAUGUCUUAAAUUGUUUUCUAAACUUCCAUAUUUGAUAGGAUUUGUAACAUUUAUUUAUAAUUAAUAUUGUACUGUUAAAAUCAUAUCUUUUAUGUUAUAAUGUAAAGUUAUUUUGAGCUGUUUGAAACAUUGUGAAGCAGUGGGACAGCUACAGUAGUUUCUAUAAAAACUAAACAGUAACAUUUAUAUAUUGCAUCAGGAGUAUUUUAUUCUAUAUAUAAUAUAUAUAUAUGGUAAAUAUCUGUUUUAUAAAUAUAUUCAUUUAAAGAAAGUAUCGUUAUGACACUAUCUGCCAUAUUUUUAUACAUUUGUGAUAUGAAGUGAGUAUUAUACUUCUACUAAAGGGAGUUGAAUUGUGGCUACACGUGACUGUAACAGUAUGAACCUUGCUCAACUUUGAGGCCCCAGCAGUAGCCUCUAGACAUGAUCCUUGGUAGCAGACGAGAUGCAGCAUCUCUUUCCAAACCUGCAGGGGAAGAAAGUCAGAUAGGCCAGUGAGAAUUCCAGCAGGCCUGGUUUCCGUCCUCACACACUUGGCUCCUGUUUGUGUCCAGGGACGUUACUUGCACACAGGGGAGAAUAGAUUGAGGCGUUACUCGUGGGUCUUUGUAGAGAGAAUGUGCUCUUCCACUUAGCAUUAGUGUAGAGCGUAGACCAAAGAUUUGCCAGUGAACAUUCCUUGUUGUGAGAUCAUAAGAGGUACCUGUCUGCAGAUCUUGCAAACCAUCUCUAUGCUCCUGAAUAUUGUCCACUGUCCCGGAGACUCUUGGCUGAUGGGGUGUGAGAUAUAUGUGUGGCAUUUCUAUUUCUGAAUGCCUUUUUUGCUAUUGCUCUCUCCAAUACCAUAUUUAAAAGGCUCCUGGAGCAAUUCCAGAUAGAUAAAAAAUUACUCUAUCCAUUUUUUUCUUCCUGGGGCUGUCCACUUAUGACAAGAUUUUCAUGCACACCUGUUACGCACACAACCCCCAUCAGAACAGGACCUAUCUUCCCCUCAUCUGAUCUCUUUCAGCUCCCAAGUUACUCCCAAGUAUCAUCAAACCCUUUGGCCAUCAAGUGUUAUCCUCCCAUGCCUCUGGGUCAUCCUUGAGGGAAGUCACCUCAGCACCAUCAUCUAUCAGUAGUAGUAGAUUUUUGGAAUUAGUCUCUGAGCAAUAAUACUUUUAAAGGUCCCUCCCACCCCUCAAAGAGAUAACUUCUCAGUAUUUAUUACUUGUCCUCAAAUUCUGAGUGUCAGCCCCUGCAUCAAGUCAGCUAUGAUCAAAAUGUGCUGUUACUGUUAACCCUCCCCCGAGAUUUUGAGAAUCAUAGCUCUGAUGAUUAUGAAGAUUAUAAAGACUAAGGUCCUAGUUUCCCUGAAGCUUAAAUUGUGCACAUAUUGCAUUUUUAUAUAAAUACUAUAAUGUGUAUUGAUUAUAUAGAUAGGUCAUUUUAAGGUGCUUUUUAUUUAAUUUUAAUGAGUGUAAUAGGCACUAAAAUGAAACUCGACUGGGUACUAUUACUGAAAAAAUUUGACUCAAACCAAUAGUUUUGCAUGCUCUUUAGUUCUUUUUCUGUCUUACUUCUUUCACCAGUUCAGUACUGUUUGGGUAGCUCUGAAUUCUGGCUUUUCCAGGCAGCUGCUUGAUGAUACAAAUGAGGUGGACCAUCAGCAGUUUUGCCUGGACACUAAUGACUCUAAAAGGGUGUGUAUUUAACUCUUCUUUUUCAUACUAGAUCUCUACCUUGUAUUCCCCCCUUGCAAACCAGAAACUACACUUUUUUUCUCUGGAAAGACUUCUCACUGUGCUAUGCGCUUAGGAACUGCACGGUCCCGUUGCCAUGCUGUGGCAUUCGAGGCUCGUCACCUAGGGGCUGGUUUCCCAUGUUGUCAUCCUUGCUAACACUGGGAUCUCAGAUGUUUGCAGAACAUUUCUAUUCAUGACGGUUCUUCAAAGAAGGGCUAGAAUAUUUGCCUUCUACCUAGAGCAAAGUAAACCUAAUUGUUGAAGAGUCAAUACGUACUUUUUGUACUUUCCCAGAUUUGAGCCAGAAAAUACCUACAGAUAUCUACAAAUGUUUUCAACCAGUGUUUUCGAGGUAGCUCUUUAAUCCUCUUCUCAGCUUUUGUCUGUUCUGACUUUUCAUCCAAUAAGCUGUAAGUGAACUACAAUCUGCAUUUCCAGCAUGCAAUUCUCUUCCUGCUCACGGAGGGGGAUGCAAAAGUUUUCUCUCACACCUAAUGGGCCCUCUCUUAGCUUUUAACUGUUGUUUUCCCCUGUUGAUGAAAAAUUACUGACAUCACAAAGAUUGCCAUCCAUGGUAGAAAGGACUUGAUUUAAAGUCAGAAAAAUUUGCCUUUUCUUUAGGAAGGGGAAUUCAUGACAUCCAUGUCCUAUUAUCGGCCGUAACUUCCUAAAGAAGAAAAAGGGUGAAUGAAAGCUUAUGUUACUUUUAUGAAAGUAUCACUGAUCUCCUUUGGAAAAGAAACUCUGCUUCACUGUUUUUCUACCUUUAUUUCUCUGCCAUCCUCGUUUUUCCUCUCUGAAGUUCUAAAUACCCUUUAACUGAACCUUGUUGGUCUUGCUCUAAAAUUUAGCCUCUUUCUAGAGCCCAAGACCAAAAGGGAGUGCUUCAUGCUGAGGGGCUCAAGUGAGCUGACUCUACAACUGUGGUUCUCAACUAGGGGCAGAUUUACCCCCAAGGGUACAUUUGGCAAUGUCUGGGGACAUUUGGUUGUCAUAGCUGGGGGGGAGGUGAUGGUAUGCUACUGGCAUCAAGUGGUUAGAGGCCACAGAUGCUACUAAACACCCUGCCAUGCACAGGACAGCCCCCCAAACAAACAGUGGUCCAGCCCCAAGCACUACUAGUGCUGAGGUUGAGAAACCCUGCCCUACACCAUCCCAAGCCCACCAGUCUGCAGAGCUUGGCUCUGGCCUUGUUCUGUCCAGGCUACAGUACUGCAGGUGUGAUUUCUUCAACAUCACAUUCUCUUAAGAGUCUUCAACCACUAUGCCUGAAUCCUUGGAAUCCUAUUGUUCGUUUCCAUUGUCUUGGGCCUGCUAAAAGGUGCAUACUUUGGAAGGAGACCAGAGUUACUUUAUAGGUGUUGGAGAACUUAAAUUCUAGGUUAGCAUCCUUAGAAAAUCUUUCAUAGAGCCAUGAGGCUUAUAUUUAGAAGCAAGCAACAGCCUGGCAGAUUGGCAUGAUUUUUACCAACUGCUCAAAGGCAUCCGUGGCUUUCAGCUGUGUCUCCCGAAAGAAAAUGUCUUUGUUUUUUAUUCAAGUCAUUUAAUAGCUCUUUACAAAUAUUAGCAUAUGGCAGACCAAUUAGAAGCAAAAAAGUCCGUAUUGGUGGUUGUGAUGUGGCUGUUAUAGAAGUAUUUGUGCUGUAUGCUUUGGUUAAAUCUGUUUUAAAACAUGCUUUAAGAUUCACCUUACGCAGUUGUACUUUAAUUCUAAGCUCAGAGCUAUGCUGUCAGUCUCUAGUCACGCCAUGUAUUAUAAAGUAUGUUGUGGUUGUAGAGUUAGCCAGUUUAGCAUGUUCCUAAUCUGAGAAUUAGUGGACUAUACUAGGAAAUGCUAUCCCAUUUUCCCUUUCCAGCCCCUCUUAGUUAAGAUCAUAGUAUCCUCACUUCUUAAACUAGUCUUUAGAGUAAAUAAGGAAAAAAGCCAUUUAUUUUCUUCUAGCCAUGUAUUAUUGAGAAUGACUCAUAGUACAACUUUUUUUCAAAGGCCAGAGGAUUACUUUGCAAGUGUGUAGAAAGAUCUGUCUAUUUCUGUUCACCUGGGACCUGGUGGUGACUGAACUCUUUCAGCAAGGGCAAUGGCUCAAUGUGAUUCGGUGCUGGAGCUCAGCUGGGACUCAGUAAAUCUGCACGUUCUCUGCUGGUCAGAACAUGUUUCCUGGAGAGCAUUGCUUUUCUAUCUAGAAGUUCGUUACCUCCUGCAUGAUAGUGGGAUAUUGAGAUGUGGGUUCUAAGAUCCACAGACUCAUACUUUUGUGAACUUUGGAAUGUGGUAGGGUACACUGAACCAAGUCAGAAAAUAGUGAAAUAUUUCCUUGCCUCCUUCAGUUCAUCACUAAGAAAGUGUGUAGGCAGAGAAAACUUACUUAUGGUUUGAAGAACCACAAUUGUUUUUGAAAGGGGACAUAGAAAAGACAGUACAAAGGUUGUAAGUGUCCUGUCGCUAAUUCCCAGGGCCAGAAUCUCACAAGAAGAUCCUCUCAAAGACUUAAAAGCCUGGCUUACAAAAAUAACCAGAAACCAAACUUGUAAGCAGUUACAAUUUCUUCCUUUUGCUUCUUGACCAGCUGAGAUACAGAAUAUCUUGAGGUCUGGUUCAGCUGAUGAAAAAUUCUGUCUCAGAAACGAUGAGUAAGAAACCAUACAAGAAAAAGAAGUCCCUCAUCUAUCUGCAUACACGCAAUGUGGGAGAAGUGGGGUGGCUAGGAAACUCUGGGCCUGCUGCCCCCUUCGAUUCUUUUUUUUUUUCUUUGUGAAUUGAAUGUACGAUACAAAUGGUAGGCCUUCAUGUGAGCCAGUUACUACAUGAAUCUUCAUUUCCCACAGUGGUUUGUUCAUUCAUCAGCGUUAGGCUUGGUCCUGGCUCCACCUUUCUCCUCUCCGGGCACUGACCCCACCUUUCCGUGUAUUUACUGUAGGCUAUUAAAUAUGAUCAUGACCCGCCUUGCAUUUUCAUUCAUCACCUGUUUAUGCCCAAAUUUAAAGGAAGUUUGUCUCAUUUUGCCAGAAAAAAAUUGUAAUAGUCGGCACGCUGGAUUUGUAGGGCCAGCAAAAUUGCGGCAGUGAAACUAGUUUCACUUCUAAAGCCCUUCAUUUCCCACAAGGUUAAGCUCUCGAAACCCCAUUUGAUCCUUGGUUCCUAUUUCGAUCCUCCUUUGGAAUCUGAAAAUCGGUCUCCAUGUUGUAUGCAGAUUAGAAGUUGCCUUGUUUGUUACUCUUCCAACACAGGGUAUCAGGGAGAAAGAGGCCUUAUCUGUUCCUCCAUCCCCCCUGUUUUGACAGACUGCUAAGAAUUCCUCAGGACUUCCUUUGGUUGGGGAUUUUACUUUCCCAAAAGUCUGAUCUGAUUUCUUUCAGGGGUAGACAAGCUUGUCCUAGUGCUCUGCUUCAGGUCUUAUCAGAAGAAACCCAGGAAUAGAAAAGGUAGAUGCCUUGACUUUUGUCCCUGUUGUGGGGACUAAAGUGUUUUUUGCCAGAAUUGUCAAAAGCUCCGGUUCAAACUCUGUAGAGUUUCAUGGAAAAACAAAACAAAACAAAAAAGAUGCUUAUCGUCCCGGAGAAUGUGUAAGUAAGUUCUCCAGCACGGCUUAGGUUUUCCAAAAUGGAAAGCAAAGCUUGCAGACAACCUGUUUUCUCUAGAGACACACAAUGAUUCUGGCCCUCAGUCUGUUUCCCUCCCCUUGUUUACUCUUUGGUCACCGAUCGAGUCAGGCUAGAGGGGUAAUACGGUGAUUAAAAGAAGUAAAUUCUCACUGUAAACUUGGAUUGAUUAACAGAAACAAUUAAACCAAACAAAAUCAUUGCCCCAAAUUUCUAUCUCCAAGAAUUGCUUUGUGCCAUUUUGAAUUCAGGUAGUUAUUCUGUAUAUACUUAGCUAACUAUUCAGAGCUUCUUCAAUCUCUAGUAAGCUUGAAGGUGGUGUCUGGGAAGACACAGGGCAGGGUGACAUUUAGACUCUGUUCAUUCUUAAAAAUAGGGAUAAGCCAGAAUGAUGUGACAUCUAGUAUGUGGUAGAUGAAGAAUCAGUGGAAAUUCUUAAUUGCACAGACUUUAUAAUCCAUUAUAUAAAGUGUAAUUCCAUACUUUUUACUGUGGCAAGGGUGUGAUGUGAUUGUUAAUCUUUUUAAUUUUUGAAUCCAAACUGAAUUUAAAGUGUUGAAUACUUAAAUCCUCACAAGUGAAUUAUGAACCAUUUGUAAAGUGUUUCUAUAACUCUUUGUAUCAUGUGUUGGUACAUCUUAUCAAGUUUUUUCUGGCAUGUAAUUCCAUUCUAAACUUAUGUAAAAUUUCUAUUGUUGCUGUAAAUAUUACACAAAUAUCUAUUCCGUGAUAACCUUCAUUAUCAGCAUGAAAUGGUUAAUUUUUACUGAGCACAAUGUAUUUUUGAAUGGAUCUUCCCAAAUGUCUUUAAUAAAAUGCAGAUUUUGCACUGACUGAUGUGACUGCCAGGCCGUCCCAAUCUUGAGCACUGUGGUCCUUCGUGUUUGAACUGCGAACAGCUCCAUUUUAGUUCCUUCUUGGGAAGAAAGAAUGCAUUCGAAUUCAAAUGAGGGAUGAUGGGCCUUUGAGGUUGUAAUCAGUUUGAGACAGAAAUUAAUGUAAAACUAGGCAAAUCCUGUAACUUAAUGAUGUUGAUCUUUGUUUUCCUAUUUAUAAAGCUUUUUUCCCCUUACGGCAUUUUGAAAACUUUGGUUUGUUUUAUACUUGAGUGUUGUCACCUUUGCACGUCGCUAGACACUCACGUGGUAGUUUGAGGAGGAUGGGAAGAGAGGCCAAUCUUGUGCUAAGUGCUAUGGAGAAAGCAAAGAUGCACAGCUUAAUAAGGGUUUUUUGAUUCUAGAGGAGAGGUGGGCAAGCUUUUCCUGUAAAGGGCCAGAUGGUAAAUAUUGGGGGCUCUGUGGCCCAUCAGUUCCCUGUCAACAUUACUCAGCUCUGCCUUUGUAUUGCAGAGGCUGCAUGGAUAAUAUGUAAAUCAGUAAGUGUGGCUGUGGUCCCGUAAAACUUUACUUAUAGAAACAGGCCAUAGUUUACUAACCCGUUUUAGGCCCUCAGUUUCAUCAUUUAGGGUAACACCAACCGAGUACAUGUUCAAUCAGGAGGGAAAGAACUUAGCUUUUGUGAUAACUUAUAGAUGAAAUAUUCCCCAGUUUUCUUUCUCUUUCUAAACAAAGGGUAGGAGCUGAAAGUCAGUGCUCUCCAUUCUUAAAAGUCCUCUGUCAACCACCUCUUCACUCUAUCUCCUUAAGUGACAUGGAAACUUGUGGCCUGUGCUUUCAACUAUAAUCUUACCAAGACUGAAUGAAAGUAUUUGGUGCUUAUACUUUUUAAUGUUCAUAGCACUUACUAUGGCCAGGCACAAUGCCCAAGUGUUUUGCUUUAUUAUUAUUAUUAUUAUUAUUAUUAUUAUUAUUAUUAUUAUUAUUUUCACAACAACCCAGCGAAACAGGUACUAUUAUUAUCCCCUUUUUGUAAAUGAGGAAACAGAUUUCCAUACUUGACAUUAACCUGCCCAAGGUCACCCAGUUUGGAAGUGGCAGGGCCAGGAUUUGAAGCCGAAUAUGUUCAUUGUAAAGCCCAUAUACCCUUAAAAGUCACUGCACGUCCACGUAUGGUAAUGUGGUCACAAUCAGUAUUGUUUCUCUUUAGUAAUUCAGAUUUAUUCAAGUAACUCCAAGGUUCAAAUUUUCAAAAACAGUUUCCAACACAGGUUAUAUUAAAAACUUUGCCUGAAGUUUACUCUAGGUGCAGAAAUAAAGACAACUUAGUCAAGUGAAGGAAAGGGUAACAGACUUAGAAAUGGCUAUCUACACUGAUGGAAUAAGUAUACUAAUUAGAGCAGGUAACAAGUCCCCACGAUGUAUAACAUAUUCUUCUCUAAAAGCUCACAACAAUUUAUGUGCCACCUUCCAUCCCCUUUCCCAGCAGAUGGUAAUUGAUGCAAUUUGAGAAUAGAACACUUCAUUGAAACAAGUCACUGGAGGUCCUCUGGGGAUGCAGCUUAAAAGCCCAGGAUCAGGCCAGGUGUGGUGGCUCACGCCUGUAAUCCCAGCACUGUGGGAGACUGAGACGGGCAGAUCACCUGAAGUCAGGAGUUCGAGACCAGCCUGGCCAAUAUAGAGAAACCCCGUCUGUACUAAAAAUACAAAAAUUAGGUCUGGGCGGUGGCUCACGCCCGUAAUCCUAGCACUUUGGGAGGCCAAGGUGGGUGGAUCACGAGGUCAGGAGUUCGAGACCAGCCUGGCCAACAUGGUGAAACCCCGUCUCUACUAAAAAUACAAAAAUUGGGUGUGGUGGUACAUGCCUGUAAUCCCAGCUGCUUAGGAGGCUGAGGCAGGAGAAUCACUUGAACCCAAAAGGCAGAGGUUGCAGUGAGCCGAGAUCACGCCACUGCACUCCAGCCUGGCAACAGAGCGAGACUCUGUCUCAAAAAAAAAAAAAAAAAAAUACAAAAAUUAGCCGGGAAUGGUGGUGAAUGUCUAUAAUCCCAGCCACUCGGGAGGCUGAGGCAGGAGAAUCACUUGAACCCAAAAGGCAGAGGUUGCAGUGAGCCAAGAUCGCACCACUGCACUCCCACCUGGACGACAGAGCGAGACGCCAUCUCAAAAAUAAAUAAAUAAAUAAAUCCCUAGGAUAUAGAGUCCGCUUGCCUGGGUGGAGUCUUGGCUCCAUCUCCUACAUCUCAUGUGACUUGAAGCAAGGCACUUCACUAUGCCUCAGUUUCCUUAUCUUUAAAUGGAGGUAAUCACAGUACCUACCUCAGUGUUGUUGUGAAGAUUUAAUGAGAUAAUAACCUGCAGAGCACUUGAGAGUCUCAAGAAAUAUGAGCUCUUAUAACAUUAUUGCUAUUGUAAAACAUUGCUAUUACUUCUGUCCCAAUUUGGCAGUUUCAGGAAAUUGAGAAGGAAUGUCACUGAAUCUUUAAUGCCAGUUACACAGAGCUCAGUAGGUGUCCGCACAGCCCUUUAGAUGCACGUAGCCUAUUUGAUCUUCGUAUCAGCCCUGUAAGGUUGGGCUUAAGAAUGACCCAGCAUGGAAGUACUCUUGGGACCACAGGGGAAGCAACAGUCCUUGUAAGCUGUUUGUCAGUGGGCCUUAGCAACCAAGCCCCAAGUGGACAGAAAGAUGGGGUUCUGUGAGCAUCCAUUCCAAGGGUCACUUUAGGGGUGCAAUCUUCUGGGCUCUGAGAAUGGAUUCACAGCAGCAUCUCUAUCUGGAAAUACCUUUGCUUUGUCCAAGUAACCUCCUCCCACACAGAGUACCCGAAUCAGCUCAGAUUUUUUUUCCUUAAUAUUGGCAACACUUAAUGCUACUUCUUUGUUCGUAACAUUUCAUUUAAUUAUUUAAAAAUCUGCAAAUGUUGUGUAUAUUUUACCGCAAUUUUUAAACAAACUCCAGUGUAGACCGUGCUCUAGCAUUUCUAAAAAUAAAAGUAAAUAUGUUAAAAUAAGGUAAGAGUGAGUUUUUCCUACACUAUGUAUAAUUUUUAAUUGAAAGUUUCCCCCACAAAAGAAAUGAUACUUGGAAGCAUAGUUUGUGUGUUUGACAGCAAGAUUCUAUUAGGCUUCAGAUUUCCCUCAAUAAAAGUUUUAGUUUUUAUACAUUCUGUCAUGAAUUGAAUGAAGUAAAUAAUAUGCUGUUGUAAGCAAAUUAUCUGCAGAUAAAUGUCUUAUGAAUCGUAUAUCUUACUGUUUAUUAAAUUCUGAAGUAUUGAGCAGUUUCCAAUGUGAAAUCCCAGCUGGCUUCUUUGCAAUGAUGGACAAGUUAGUUAUAAUUCAUAUGGAAAUUCAAGGAACCCAGAAUAGCCAAAACAAUCCCGAAGAGCAAAGUUGGAGGACUCACAUGCCCCAAUUUCAAAACUUACUACAAAGCUACAAUAAUGAAGAAAGUGAGGUAAUAGAAUUUGGAGUCCAGAAAUAAACCCUCUCACAUUUAUGGUCAAUUGUUUUUUGACAAGGGUGCCAAGAUCAUUCAAUGGGGGAAAGAAUAGUCUUUUCAGCAAAUAGUGGUGGGACAACUGGAUAUCCACAUGCAAAAGAAUGACGUUGGACUCCUAUUUCACACCAUAUACAAAAAUUAACUCAAAAUGGAACAAAGAUCUAACUGUAAGAGGUAGAACUAUAAAACUCAUAGAAGAAAACAUAGGGGUAAAUCUUCAUGACCUUGGAUUUGGCAGUGGUUUCUCAGAUAUGACACCAAAGGCACAAGCAAAGAGAAAAAUAAAUUGGACUUCAUCAAAUAUUUAAAAUUUUGUGCUUAAGAGGACUCUAUCGAGAGGGUUAAAAAGAUCCACAGAAUGGGAGAAAAUAUUUGCAAAUCAUAUCCAAUAAGGGAAUUAGAAUAUACAAAGAAUUCUUAAACUCAGUAAGUUGUAAGCCGAUUUAAAAUGGGCAGAGGAUCUGAAAAACCUUUAUCCAAAGAUGUACAAAUGGCCAGUAAACACAUGAAAAGAUGCUCAACAUCAUUAGUCACUAGGGAAAUGCAAAUCAAAACCACAGUUGAGAUGCAACUUCACACAUUAUGGGUAUAGUCAAAGAUGGACAGUAACAAGUGUUGCUGAGGAUGUGGAGAAAGUGGAAGCCUCCUACAUUGCUGGUGGAAAUGUAAAAUGAUGCAGCCACUUGGGAUAAUAGUUCCUCCAAAGAUUAAACAAGAGUGACUGUGUGUCCCAGCAGUUUUACUCCUAAGUAUAUACCCAAGAUAAAUGAAAACACACAUCCGCACAAAAACUUAUACACAAAUGUUCAUAGCAGCAUUAUUCAUAAUAGCUAAAGAGUGGAAACCCAAAUAUCCAUCAAUGGAUGAAUGGAUAAAUAACAAUGUGCUCUUGACAUGAUACUGAACAAUGAUGUUCAGCAAUAAAAAGGAGUGACAAGUGACAUAGUGAUACACAUGUUAUAACGUGGAUGAACUUUAAAACACUAUGCUAAGUGAAAGAAGCCAGUCACGAAAUACCACAUACUAUAUGAUUUCAUUUAUGUAGAACGUCCAGAAGGCCAAUCUACAGAGACAGUCGAUUCGUGGUUGCAGAGGGCUUGGGGUGGCCGAUGGGUUGGGGAGUGUUGGCUGAUGGGUGCAGGAUUUCUCUUUGGGGUGAUAAACUUUCUAAAAUUGAUCUAGUGAUAAUGGUUGCACAACUCUGAAUAUACCAAAAGUCAUCAAAUUGUACACUUUAAAUGGAUACAAAUUGUAUGUGAACUUAAUCUCAAUAAAGCCGUGACAAAAGUUUCCAACAUGAA